AGACGCCCGGCGCAGCGGGAGCGGCGGGGCGUGCCUGGCCUGCGGGACGCGACUGAUCGCAGUGGGGCGAAGCGGGGCCGGAGCCGCCCGCGGUCAGGAGCAGCAAUGUCUGUGCAGGUAGCGGCUCCUGGAAGUGCAGGGCUGGGCCCAGAGCGCCUGAGCCCUGAGGAGCUGGUGCGGCAGACGCGGCAAGUGGUCCAGGGGCUGGAGGCGCUGCGGGCAGAGCACCAUGGCCUGGCUGGGCACCUGGCGGAGGCCCUGGCGGGACAGGGCCCGGCAGCCGGCUUGGAGAUGCUGGAGGAAAAGCAGCAGGUGGUGAGCCACUCGCUGGAGGCCAUCGAGCUGGGGCUGGGCGAGGCCCAGGUGCUGCUGGCCCUGUCGGCACAUGUGGGUGCACUGGAGGCAGAGAAGCAGCGGCUGCGCUCGCAGGCCCGGCGGCUGGCCCAGGAGAACGUGUGGCUGCGGGAGGAACUGGAGGAGACGCAGCGGCGGCUUCGGGCCAGCGAGGAGUCCGUGGCCCAGCUGGAGGAGGAGAAGCGCCACCUGGAGUUCCUGGGGCAGCUGCGACAGUACGACCCACCGGCGGAGAGCCAGCAGUCUGAGUCCCCGCCUCGCCGAGACAGCCUGGCCUCCCUGUUCCCCAGCGAGGAGGAGGAGAGGAAAGGUCCUGAGGCCGCAGGAGCAGCAGCUGCUCAGCAGGGUGGCUAUGAGAUCCCUGCCCGCCUUCGGACCCUGCAUAACCUCGUGAUCCAGUACGCGGGGCAGGGCCGCUAUGAGGUGGCGGUGCCUCUGUGCCGCCAGGCCUUGGAGGACCUGGAGCGCAGCUCGGGCCACUGCCACCCUGACGUGGCCACCAUGCUCAACAUCCUGGCGCUGGUGUACCGGGACCAGAACAAGUACAAAGAAGCCACAGACCUUCUCCAUGAUGCCCUGCAGAUCCGGGAGCAGACGCUGGGCCCUGAGCACCCCGCGGUGGCCGCCACGCUCAACAACUUGGCUGUCCUCUAUGGGAAGCGUGGGCGUUACCGGGAGGCAGAGCCCCUGUGCCAGCGCGCUUUGGAGAUCCGAGAGAAGGUCCUGGGUGCUGACCACCCAGAUGUGGCCAAGCAGCUCAACAACCUGGCCCUGCUGUGCCAGAACCAGGGCAAGUUUGAGGACGUGGAGCGGCACUAUGCCCGGGCCCUGAGCAUCUAUGAGGCACUGGGCGGGCCCCAUGACCCCAACGUGGCCAAGACCAAGAACAACCUGGCCUCAGCCUACCUGAAACAGAACAAGUAUCAACAAGCGGAAGAGCUGUACAAAGAAAUCCUCCACAAGGAGGACCUACCCGCCCCUCUCGGUGCCCCCAACACAGGCACAGCUGGUGACGCAGAACAGGCCCUUCGCCGCAGCAGCUCACUCUCCAAGAUCCGUGAGUCUAUCAGGCGAGGAAGUGAGAAGCUGGUCUCCCGGCUCCGAGGCGAGGCGGCGGCAGGAGCAGCCGGAAUGAAGAGAGCCAUGUCACUCAACACACUGAACGUGGAUGCUCCAAGGGCUCCUGGGACUCAGUUUCCCAGCUGGCACCUGGACAAGGCCCCUCGGACCCUCAGCGCCAGCACCCAGGACCUGAGCCCCCACUAACGUCCAGUGAACUGCGCUGGCCGCAGCUUCUUGGGAACAGUGCAGGAGGGAUGGGCUGGUGGGGUGAGAGGGGGUCUAUCAUCUCCUGGCCCCCCCUUGCCUCUGGGUACCUGGUGGAUAGCUGCCUUCUCCUGCGAUUAAAGGCUGUGGACGUGACAGUGA